CUGGAUGGAGUAUUUUCUGGGUGUCUCUAAUGAGUAAGAGAGGGCCCCAUGGGAUAUUCCUUCAGUUCCCAGAUGAACAGUGGGAAAGACUCCACAUUGACCAACCUCGGGGGCCUGAAAACCCAGGUCCUCAAGGAGGGUAGAGUAUACCUGGACCCUGACCCAGACCCCUGGAUGGGCUGUGCCAAGAGACCCAGCAAGGGAAGGGAUUUCCUCCUGCCUCAGGUUCUCUGUUCUUCUGUGGUUAGACCACCUGAACCCAACUCCCUCCCCAAGCACUAGAGAUGGGCUUUUCCAAGGGCUGGGGAUCUUGCUGUCCUGAGGACAGCUGAGCAAGGGGGUCGAGGAGGAGCUUGGGUUGUGGAGGAGAGGAAACCGGGUAAGAUGCGUGAAGCAGUUGGCUAUACCAGGCACAGAGAGGACCCGCUGGGACCCAAGAGCCUGCAUGUGAAGCCAGGCCUUGGGCCACCUUGUCUGUCAAGGGGGUGCCUACUUCCAUGGUGUCUUCAAAGGGACUGUGGAAAGAGAGGCCUUCAGCCCACACCUCUGAAUGCUUUUCCACCACAGCAUGCCCUGUGGCCUUUAUCCUGCUGGUGUGGAACAGUCAGACCCCUGCAGGGCUGCAGAGCCUCUGUACUGGGCGGCAUCCCAGCCUGAGUGCCAGAGCUCAGAGGGCAGGCCCCCGAGCAAGCAGAGAGGAGGGCACCUUUUGGACAGAACGUGUGGGACAAGAGCGAUGGCUCAUCCGUUCAGGUUCCUCACAAAAUGAGAGUCAGGAAGAUCAGGGCGCCGGCCUGAUUUCCCAGGCAGGGCUGAAAGCAGACAACCGGAGGGAGAGCAGCACCUGGGCCAAUGAGGUAGAAGACAGAAGACCACAGUGUACUCCUGCCCUCAACCUCACCCCCUCCCACCCACAUCCUCCACACUCCCUGACCACCUUCCUCAGAAGUGUAAUAGGAAUCCAGAUUCCCCCUGGCCUGGUUGCUGCAGGAGGCACAGUAGCCUGA